AGAUUGUGAAGGGUUCCUGAGUAAGCAGCGUGUCUCCAUCCCCCUCUCUAGGGGCUCUUGGAUGGACCUUGCACUCUAGAAGGGACAAUGGACUUCUGGCUUUGGCCACUUUACUUCCUGCCAGAGAUGGAGUCUUGCUGUGUUGCCCAGGAUGGUCUUGAACUUGUGGCCUUAAGUGAUCCUCCUGGCUCAGCUUCACAAAGCGCUGGGAUUACAGUAUCGGGGGCCCUGAGGAUCCUCCCAGAAGUAAAGGUAGAGGGGGAGCUGGGCGGAUCAGUUACCAUCAAGUGCCCACUUCCUGAAAUGCAUGUGAGGAUAUAUCUGUGCCGGGAGAUGGCUGGAUCUGGAACAUGUGGUACCGUGGUAUCCACCACCAACUUCAUCAAGGCAGAAUACAAGGGCCGAGUUACUCUGAAGCAAUACCCACGCAAGAAUCUGUUCCUAGUGGAGGUAACACAGCUGACAGAAAGUGACAGCGGAGUCUAUGCCUGCGGAGCGGGCAUGAACACAGACCGGGGAAAGACCCAGAAAGUCACCCUGAAUGUCCACAGUGAAUACGAGCCAUCAUGGGAAGAGCAGCCAAUGCCUGAGACUCCAAAAUGGUUUCAUCUGCCCUAUUUGUUCCAGAUGCCUGCAUAUGCCAGUUCUUCCAAAUUCGUAACCAGAGUUACCACACCAGCUCAAAGGGGCAAGGUCCCUCCAGUUCACCACUCCUCCCCCACCACCCAAAUCACCCACCGCCCUCGAGUGUCCAGAGCAUCUUCAGUAGCAGGUGACAAGCCCCGAACCUUCCUGCCAUCCACUACAGCCUCAAAAAUCUCAGCUCUGGAGGGGCUGCUCAAGCCCCAGACGCCCAGCUACAACCACCACACCAGGCUGCACAGGCAGAGAGCACUGGACUAUGGCUCACAGUCUGGGAGGGAAGGCCAAGGAUUUCACAUCCUGAUCCCGACCAUCCUGGGCCUUUUCCUGCUGGCACUUCUGGGGCUGGUGGUGAAAAGGGCCGUUGAAAGGAGGAAAGCCCUCUCCAGGCGGGCCCGCCGACUGGCCGUGAGGAUGCGCGCCCUGGAGAGCUCCCAGAGGCCCCGCGGGUCGCCGCGACCGCGCUCCCAAAACAACAUCUACAGCGCCUGCCCGCGGCGCGCUCGUGGAGCGGACGCUGCAGGCACAGGGGAGGCCCCCGUUCCCGGCCCCGGAGCGCCGUUGCCCCCCGCCCCGCUGCAGGUGUCUGAAUCUCCCUGGCUCCAUGCCCCAUCUCUGAAGACCAGCUGUGAAUACGUGAGCCUCUACCACCAGCCUGCCGCCAUGAUGGAGGACAGUGAUUCAGAUGACUACAUCAAUGUUCCUGCCUGACAACUCCCCAGCUAUCCCCCAACCCCAGGCUCGGACUGUGGUGCCAAGGAGUCUCAUCUAUCUGCUGAUGUCCAAUACCUGCUUCAUGUGUUCUCAGAGCCCUCAUCACUUCCCAUGCCCCAUCUCGACUCCCAUCCCCAUCUAUCUGUGCCCUGAGCAUGGCUCUGCCCCCAGGUCGUCUUGCACACCUUGGCAGCCCCCUGUAGUUGACAGGUAAGCUGUAGGCAUGUAGAGCAAUUGUCCCAAUGCCACUUGCUUCCUUUCCAAGCCGUCGAACAGACUGUGGGAUUUGCAGAGUGUUUCUUCCAUGUCUUUGACCACAGGGUUGUUGCUGCCCAGGCUCUAGAUCACAUGGCAUCAGGCUGGGGCAGAGGCAUAGCUAUUGUCUCGGGCAUCCUUCCCAGGGUUGGGUCUUACACAAAUAGAAGGCUCUUGCUCUGAGUUAUGUGACAUGCCUCAGCCCCAUGGACUAAGCAGGGGUCUGGUAUAAAAACACUCCUGGAAACGCCUUUGCCCUGAUCCAAAUGUUAGCACUUGCUAGUGAACGUCUACUUAUCUCAAGUUCUAUGCUAAAGGCAAUUUAUCUUGAUGUGAUGAUAAACCAAACUUAUUAGCAAGAUAUGCAUAUAUAUCCAUAAAUUCUCUUUACUCUGUCUCCAUCACUUGAUGCACAUAAGUGCCCUGACCUCAGCAUCUCCCCUCUAAAAAAAAAAAAAAAAAAGUAUCUCUUUAUCUUUCUUCCAUAGCCUGACACUGAUAUUUGUGCACUUACCUUAACUUUGGUCUAUUUUAUUCAUCCAAAACCAUUACAUUUCUUGGUUUUCACAAAUGUUCCCCAUUUCUUAGCCAGUUCCAGACAAUGUAUAGCAAGCAGGGGAAGGAAAGCAGUCAGGAGUUCCUGGGUGGCCACGGCUCUGCAAUAGCACUUAUGUCAUGGAAGUGAUAUCCCACCUCCUACAUAUACUCUUUGCCUAGGUUUUUGGAACAAGGUUAUAGUCAGACACUGUAUCUUUAGAUUGAUGUCGACCACAAAGUUCAGCCAGAGCUUGAGGCUAGAUGCACAGCCUUGCUAUUGGGAAGAAGGCCUUUUCUAGCUGUACAACACAGUCUCACUGGGCAUUCAUCCAGAAAUAGAGAAGAAAGUCUGCCAGACUUGAGUUAUGUUGUCUUUUAUUAGCAGGGAAUGUCAUCACAGAUUGGAUAGUACAUCCAGGUGCAAUGUCACCAUCAGCAAGGUCAGCUUGACACUCAAGUGGAAGAUUAGGGAAGAAUGACUAGGAUAAAAAAAAAAGGAGGGCACCAAGGGAAAGGGAUGAUGGGGUGAGCUGGCGAGUGUGGGUGGGAAAUGAAAUGUUUAUUGAGGAUCUGCUUUGUGCUGGGCACUUUAAUCCACAUUUUAUCGUUUACUUUUCAAACAGAUGCACCUUACCCCCACCCCAAUGCUCUGUCCCUGCAGAUAUCAGAAGACAGUGUGAUUUUCAUGCUCUGAAGUUCAGUUUUACAUCCAAGCAUCCCUCUCUGUUUUUUAACAAUCCAAAGACAGGCCAAAAAAAGCACCACAGUUUAUUAAGUACUUACUAAGCACCCAUCCACUGCCCCACACUGUGGCAAGGAUUGUGAGGGGUAAAGAAGCAUGGGGCACAAUAUUCUGCUGCCUUCAUGUAACUUACAGUCUCACAAAUAAAUAGAACUUCAGUUGAAA